AAUGGGCCAGGGCUCUGCGCGGAUAGAGGAGCGGGCGCCGGGACCGGGAAUCCCCGAGCUGCGCCUUCUGGGGACGCGGCCCGGGCUACGUCGGGGCCGUCCGUGGGGAGCGGGGUCCUGGAGGCUGCGCGGGGCUGAGGCGGCCUCGAUUUGGGAACUGCCUGAAGAUGCCGGCCUAAGCCUGGAGUCCAGGCAUGGACUUCCCCACAAUUUCCCGAUCCCCUUCGGGGCCUCCAGCCAUGGACUUGGAGGGGCCCAGGGACAUUCUUGUGCCUUCGGAGGACCUCACCCCUGACAGCCAGUGGGACCCUAUGCCAGGAGGCCCCGGCAGCCUCAGUCGGAUGGAACUUGAUGAGUCAAGCCUUCAGGAGCUGGUGCAGCAGUUUGAAGCUCUGCCAGGCGAUCUGGUGGGCCCAUCCCCAGGUGGAGCCCCCUGUCCCCUACACAUUGCCACAGGCCAUGGCCUGGCCUCCCAGGAGAUUGCUGAUGCCCACGGGCUCCUGUCUGCCGAAGCUGGCCGGGAUGACCUGCUGGGCCUCUUGCACUGCGAGGAAUGCCCGCCUUCCCAGACUGGUCCUGAAGAGCCUCUAGAGCCUGCCCCCCGACUGUUGCAGCCCCCUGAGGACCCAGAUGAGGAUUCUGACUCCCCAGAAUGGGUGGAGGGGGCCUCUGCUGAGCAGGAGGGCAGCAGGAGCUCAAGCAGUUCCCCGGAACCCUGGCUGGAGACGGUGCCUCUAGUCACACCUGAAGAGCCACCCGCUGGUGCCCAGAGCCCCGAGACCCUGGCUUCCUACCCUGCCCCCCAGGAGGUGCCUGGUCCCUGUGACCAUGAAGACCUCCUGGACGGUGUCAUAUUUGGGGCCAGGUACCUGGGGUCCACCCAGCUGGUGUCGGAACGGAACCCGCCCACCAGCACGCGCAUGGCCCAGGCCCGGGAGGCCAUGGACCGCGUCAAGGCCCCCGAUGGGGAGACCCAGCCCAUGACGGAGGUGGACCUGUUCGUCUCCACCAAGAGGAUCAAGGUCUUGACAGCGGACUCCCAGGAGGCCAUGAUGGACCACGCCCUGCAUACCAUCUCCUACACAGCCGACAUCGGCUGCGUGCUGGUGCUGAUGGCGCGGCGGCGGCUGGCACGGAGGCCGGCACCCCAGGACCACGGCCGCCGCCUCUACAAGAUGCUCUGCCACGUAUUCUACGCGGAGGACGCCCAGCUCAUCGCCCAGGCCAUUGGCCAGGCCUUCGCCGCCGCCUACAGCCAGUUCCUACGGGAAAGCGGUAUUGACCCCAGCCAGGUGGGCGUGCACCCGAGCCCAGGCGCCUGCCACCUCCAUAAUGGGGACCUGGACCACUUCUCCAACAGUGACAACUGCCGGGAGGUGCACCUCGAGAAGCGGCGAGGGGAGGGCCUGGGCGUGGCCCUGGUGGAGUCGGGCUGGGGCUCCCUGCUGCCCACAGCCGUCAUCGCCAACCUGCUGCACGGGGGGCCUGCUGAGCGCUCGGGGGCCCUCAGCAUCGGGGACCGCCUGACCGCCAUCAACGGGACCAGCCUGGUGGGGCUGCCCCUGGCUGCGUGCCAGGCCGCUGUCCGCGAGACGAAGUCGCAGACGUCGGUGACACUCAGCAUCGUCCACUGCCCUCCCGUCACCACCGCCAUCAUCCACCGGCCCCACGCCCGCGAGCAGCUGGGCUUCUGCGUGGAGGACGGCAUCGUGAGGCCCCGGCCCCUGGCCCCGGGGUGGGGGGGUAGGGCGGCCCUGAGCACGGCCCCUGAGCAGCCCCCACCUCUUUCCCGUCCCCCUCUUUUCUCCCCCAGAUCUGCAGCCUCCUCCGUGGUGGCAUCGCCGAGCGUGGGGGCAUCCGCGUCGGCCACCGCAUCAUUGAGAUCAAUGGGCAGAGUGUGGUGGCCACGCCACACGCCCGCAUCAUCGAGCUGCUCACCGAGGCCUAUGGCGAGGUGCAUAUCAAGACGAUGCCAGCUGCCACAUAUCGCCUCCUUACAGGCCAGGAGCAGCCCGUGUACCUGUGACCACCUCAUCCCUUGCCUGCCACUGUGCCUUCGCCUCCAUGGCCCCGGAGCCCCAUCCUGGGCCUGCCCUGGCUGGCCAGGACCCCAGCGGUUCUUGGUCCUGUAUGAUUUCCUAAUAUAAAAACAGUAAAAGCUUAUGCAUUUGGCAAAGUCUCGGAUCAGGGUCUACGGGACCGAGGACCUUGUCCUUCCUGGAAGCCACUAGAAGCCGGUGCUGUGAAAAUACUCUGUUUAUUAAAGACCAGGCGGAGGGA